GCGCGCGUCCUCACCCCCUCCUUCCCCGCGGGCGGCGGCCAGGCUCCCUCCCCUCCCCUUCCCUCUCCUCCCCUCCCCUCCCCUCUCUUCCCCUACCCUCCCGCGCGCCCGGGCCGCCGGCCGGGCCCGGGCCUGGGGGCGGGGCGGGAAGACGGCGGCCGGGAGUGUUUUCAGUUCCGCCUCCAAUCGCCCAUUCCCCUCUUCCCCUCCCAGCCCCCUCCAUCCCAUCGGAAGAGGAAGGAACAAAAGGUCCCGGACCCCCCGGAUCUGACGGGGCGGGACCUGGCGCCACCUUGCAGGUUCGAUACAAGAGGCUGUUUUCCUAGCGUGGCUUGCUGCCUUUGGUAAGAACAUGUCGUCCAUCUUGCCAUUCACGCCGCCAGUUGUGAAGAGACUGCUGGGAUGGAAGAAGUCAGCUGGUGGGUCUGGAGGAGCAGGCGGAGGAGAGCAGAAUGGGCAGGAAGAAAAGUGGUGUGAGAAAGCAGUGAAAAGUCUGGUGAAGAAGCUAAAGAAAACAGGACGAUUAGAUGAGCUUGAGAAAGCCAUCACCACUCAAAACUGUAAUACUAAAUGUGUUACCAUACCAAGCACUUGCUCUGAAAUUUGGGGACUGAGUACACCAAAUACGAUAGAUCAGUGGGAUACAACAGGCCUUUACAGCUUCUCUGAACAAACCAGGUCUCUUGAUGGUCGUCUCCAGGUAUCCCAUCGAAAAGGAUUGCCACAUGUUAUAUAUUGCCGAUUAUGGCGCUGGCCUGAUCUUCACAGUCAUCAUGAACUCAAGGCAAUUGAAAACUGCGAAUAUGCUUUUAAUCUUAAAAAGGAUGAAGUAUGUGUAAACCCUUACCACUAUCAGAGAGUUGAGACACCAGUUUUGCCUCCAGUAUUAGUGCCCCGACACACCGAGAUCCUAACAGAACUUCCGCCUCUGGAUGACUAUACUCACUCCAUUCCAGAAAACACUAACUUCCCAGCAGGAAUUGAGCCACAGAGUAAUUAUAUUCCAGAAACGCCACCUCCUGGAUAUAUCAGUGAAGAUGGAGAAACAAGUGACCAACAGUUGAAUCAAAGUAUGGACACAGGCUCUCCAGCAGAACUAUCUCCUACUACUCUUUCCCCUGUUAAUCAUAGCUUGGAUUUACAGCCAGUUACUUACUCAGAACCUGCAUUUUGGUGUUCGAUAGCAUAUUAUGAAUUAAAUCAGAGGGUUGGAGAAACCUUCCAUGCAUCACAGCCCUCACUCACUGUAGAUGGCUUUACAGACCCAUCAAAUUCAGAGAGGUUCUGCUUAGGUUUACUCUCCAAUGUUAACCGAAAUGCCACGGUAGAAAUGACAAGAAGGCAUAUAGGAAGAGGAGUGCGCUUAUACUACAUAGGUGGGGAAGUUUUUGCUGAGUGCCUAAGUGAUAGUGCAAUCUUUGUGCAGAGCCCCAAUUGUAAUCAGAGAUAUGGCUGGCACCCUGCAACAGUGUGUAAAAUUCCACCAGGCUGUAAUCUGAAGAUCUUCAACAACCAGGAAUUUGCUGCUCUUCUGGCUCAGUCUGUUAAUCAGGGUUUUGAAGCCGUCUAUCAGCUAACUAGAAUGUGCACCAUAAGAAUGAGUUUUGUGAAAGGGUGGGGAGCAGAAUACCGAAGGCAGACGGUAACAAGUACUCCUUGCUGGAUUGAACUUCAUCUGAAUGGACCUCUACAGUGGUUGGACAAAGUAUUAACUCAGAUGGGAUCCCCUUCAGUGCGUUGCUCAAGCAUGUCAUAAAGCUUCACCAAUCAAGUCCCAUGAAAAGACUUAAUGUAACAACUCUUCUGUCAUAGCAUUGUGUGUGGUCCCUAUGGACUGUUUACUAUCCAAAAGUUCAAGAGAGAAAACAGCACUUGAGGUCUCAUCAAUUAAAGCACCUUGUGGAAUCUGUUUCCUAUAUUUGAAUAUUAGAUGGGAAAAUUAGUGUCUAGAAAUACUCUCCCAUUAAAGAGGAAGAGAAGAUUUUAAAGACUUAAUGAUGUCUUAUUGGGCAUAAAACUGAGUGUCCCAAAGGUUUAUUAAUAACAGUAGUAGUUAUGUGUACAGGUAAUGUAUCAUGAUCCAGUAUCACAGUAUUGUGCUGUUUAUAUACAUUUUUAGUUUGCAUAGAUGAGGUGUGUGUGUGCGCUGCUUCUUGAUCUAGGCAAACCUUUAUAAAGUUGCAGUACCUAAUCUGUUAUUCCCACUUCUCUGUUAUUUUUGUGUGUCUUUUUUAAUAUAUAAUAUAUAUCAAGAUUUUCAAAUUAUUUAGAAGCAGAUUUUCCUGUAGAAAAACUAAUUUUUCUGCCUUUUACCAAAAAUAAACUCUUGGGGGAAGAAAAGUGGAUUAACUUUUGAAAUCCUUGACCUUAAUGUGUUCAGUGGGGCUUAAACAGUCAUUCUUUUUGUGGUUUUUUGUUUUUUUUUGUUUUUUUUUUUAACUGCUAAAUCUUAUUAUAAGGAAACCAUACUGAAAACCUUUCCAAGCCUCUUUUUUCCAUUCCCAUUUUUGUCCUCAUAAUCAAAACAGCAUAACAUGACAUCAUCACCAGUAAUAGUUGCAUUGAUACUGCUGGCACCAGUUAAUUCUGGGAUACAGUAAGAAUUCAUAUGGAGAAAGUCCCUUUGUCUUAUGCCCAAAUUUCAACAGGAAUAAUUGGCUUGUAUAAUCUAGCAGUCUGUUGAUUUAUCCUUCCACCUCAUAAAAAAUGCAUAGGUGGCAGUAUAAUUAUUUUCAGGGAUAUGCUAGAAUUACUUCCACAUAUUUAUCCCUUUUUAAAAAAGCUAAUCUAUAAAUACCGUUUUUCCAAAGGUAUUUUACAAUAUUUCAACAGCAGACCUUCUGCUCUUCGAGUAGUUUGAUUUGGUUUAGUAACCAGAUUGCAUUAUGAAAUGGGCCUUUUGUAAAUGUAAUUGUUUCUGCAAAAUACCUAGAAAAGUGAUGCUGAGGUAGGAUCAGCAGAUAUGGGCCAUCUGUUUUUAAAGUAUGUUGUAUUCAGUUUAUAAAUUGAUUGUUAUUCUACACAUAAUUAUGAAUUCAGAAUUUUAAAAAUUGGGGGAAAAGCCAUUUAUUUAGCAAGUUUUUUAGCUUAUAAGUUACCUGCAGUCUGAGCUGUUCUUAACUGAUCCUGGUUUUGUGAUUGACAAUAUUUCAUGCUCUGUAGUGAGAGGAGAUUUCCGAAACUCUGUUGCUAGUUCAUUCUGCAGCAAAUAAUUAUUAUGUCUGAUGUUGACUCAUUGCAGUUUAAACAUUUCUUCUUGUUUGCAUCUUAGUAGAAAUGGAAAAUAACCACUCCUGGUCGUCUUUUCAUAAAUUUUCAUAUUUUUGAAGCUGUCUUUGGUACUUGUUCUUUGAAAUCAUAUCCACCUGUCUCUAUAGGUAUCAUUUUCAAUACUUUCAACAUUUGGUGGUUUUCUAUUGGGUACUCCCCAUUUUCCUAUAUUUGUGUGUAUAUGUAUGUGUUCAUGUAAAUUUGGUAUAGUAAUUUUUUAUUCAUUCAACAAAUAUUUAUUGUUCACCUGUUUGUACCAGGAACUUUUCUUAGUCUUUGGGUAAAGGUGAACAAGACAACUACAGUUCCUGCCUUUGCUGAGACAGCAGUUACACUAACCCUUAAUUAUCUUACUUGUCUAUGAAGGAGAUAAACAGGGUACUGUACUGGAGAAUAACAGAUGGGAUGCUUCAGGUAGGACAUCAAGGAAAGCCUCUAAGGAAAGGAUGCAUGAGCUAACACCUGACAUUAAAGAAGCAAGCCAAGUGAGGAGCCAGGGGAGAUAAGCAUUCCUGGCAAAGAGAAUAGCAUCAAAUGCAAAAAGGUUCACACUAAAGGAAACUCCUGAUUAGGUAUUAAUGCUUUAUACAGAAACCUCUAUACAAAUCCAAACUUGAAGAUCAGAAUGGUUCUACAGUUCAUAACAUUUUGAAGGUGGCCUUAUUUUGUGAUAGUCUGCUUCAUGUGAUUCUCACUAACAUAUCUCCUUCCUCAACCUUUGCUGUAAAAAUUUCAUUUGCACCACAUCAGUACUACUUAAUUUAACAAGCUUUUGUUGUGUAAGCUCUCACUGUUUUAGUGCCCUGCUGCUUGCUUCCAGACUUUGUGCUGUCCAGUAAUUAUGUCUUCCACUACCCAUCUUGUGAGCAGAGUAAAUGUCCUAGGUAAUACCACUAUCAGGCCUGUAGGAGAUACUCAGUGGAGCCUCUGCCCUUCUUUUUCUUACUUGAGAACUUGUAAUGGUGUUAGGGAACAGUUGUAGGGGCAGAAAACAACUCUGAAAGUGGUAGAAGGUCCUGAUCUUGGUGGUUACUCUUGCAUUACUGUGUUAGGUCAAGCAGUGCCUACUAUGCUGUUUCAGUAGUGGAGCGCAUCUCUACAGUUCUGAUGCGAUUUUUCUGUACAGUAUGAAAUUGGGACUCAACUCUUUGAAAACACCUAUUGAGCAGUUAUACCUGUUGAGCAGUUUACUUCCUGGUUGUAAUUACAUUUGUGUGAAUGUGUUUGAUGCUUUUUAACGAGAUGAUGUUUUUUGUAUUUUAUCUACUGUGGCCUGAUUUUUUUUUUGUUUUCUGCCCCUCCCCCCAUUUAUAGGUGUGGUUUUCAUUUUUCUAAGUGAUAGAAUCCCCUCUUUGUUGAAUUUUUGUCUUUAUUUAAAUUAGCAACAUUACUUAGGAUUUAUUCUUCACAAUACUGUUAAUUUUCUAGGAAUGAUGACCUGAGAACCGAAUGGCCAUGCUUUCUAUCACAUUUCUAAGAUGAGUAAUAUUUUUUCCAGUAGGUUCCACAGAGACACCUUGGGGGCUGGCUUAGGGGAGGCUGUUGGAGUUCUCACUGACUUAGUGGCAUAUUUAUUCUGUACUGAAGAACUGCAUGGGGUUUCUUUUGGAAAGAGUUUCAUUGCUUUAAAAAGAAGCUCAGAAAGUCUUUAUAACCACUGGUCAACGAUUAGAAAAAUAUAACUGGAUUUAGGCCUACCUUCUGGAAUACCGCUGAUUGUGCUCUUUUUAUCCUACUUUAAAGAAGCUUUCAUGAUUAGAUUUGAGCUAUAUCAGUUAUACCGAUUAUACCUUAUAAUACACAUUCAGUUAGUAAACAUUUAUUGAUGCCUGUUGUUUGCCCAGCCACUGUGAUGGAUAUUGAAUAAUAAAAAGAUGACUAGGACGGGGCCCUGACCCUUGAGCUGUGCUUGGUCUUGUAGAGGUUGUGUUUUUUUUCCUCAGGACCUGUCACUUUGGCAGAAGGAAAUCUGCCUAAUUUUUCUUGAAAGCUAAAUUUUCUUUGUAAGUUUUUACAAAUUGUUUAAUACCUAGUUGUAUUUUUUACCUUAAGCCACAUUGAGUUUUGCUUGAUUUGUCUGUCUUUUAAACACUGUCAAAUGCUUUCCCUUUUGUUAAAAUUAUUUUAAUUUCACUUUUUUUGUGCCCUUGUCAAUUUAAGACUAAGACUUUGAAGGUAAAACAAACAAACAAACAUCAGUCUUAGUCUCUUGCUAGUUGAAAUCAAAUAAAAGAAAAUAUAUACCCAGUUGGUUUCUCUACCUCUUAAAAGCUUCCCAUAUAUACCUUUAAGAUCCUUCUCUUUUUUCUUUAACUACUAAAUAGGUUCAGCAUUUAUUCAGUGUUAGAUACCCUCUUCGUCUGAGGGUGGCGUAGGUUUAUGUUGGGAUAUAAAGUAACACAAGACAAUCUUCACUGUACAUAAAAUAUGUCUUCAUGUACAGUCUUUACUUUAAAAGCUGAACAUUCCAAUUUGCGCCUUCCCUCCCAAGCCCCUGCCCACCAAGUAUCUCUUUAGAUAUCUAGUCUGUGGACAUGAACAAUGAAUACUUUUUUCUUACUCUGAUCGAAGGCAUUGAUACUUAGACAUAUCAAACAUUUCUUCCUUUCAUAUGCUUUACUUUGCUAAAUCUAUUAUAUUCAUUGCCUGAAUUUUAUUCUUCCUUUCUACCUGACAACACACAUCCAGGUGGUACUUGCUGGUUAUCCUCUUUCUUGUUAGCCUUGUUUUUUGUUUUUUUUUUUUUUUUUUGAGAGGGAGUCUCGCUCUGUUGCCCAACCUGGAGUGCAGUGGUGCGAUCUUGGUUCACUGCAAGCUCCGCCUCCCGGGUUCACGCCAUGCUUCUGCCUCAGCCUCCCAAGUAGCUGGGACUACAGGCGCCCACCACCACACUCGGCUAAUUUUUUGUAUUUUUAGUAGAGACGGGGUUUCACCGUGUUGGCCAGGAUGGUCUCGAUCUCCUGACCUCGUGAUCUGUCCACCUCGGCUUCCCAAAGUGCUGGGAUUACAGGCAUGAGCCACCGCGCCCAGCCUAGCCAUAUUUUUAUCUGCAUAUAUCAGAAUGUUUCUCUCCUUUGAACUUAUUAACAAAAAAGGAACAUGCUUUUCAUACCUAGAGUCCUAAUUUCUUCAUCAUGAAGGUUGCUAUUCAAAUUGAUCAAUCAUUUUAAUUUUACAAAUGGCUCAAAAAUUCUGUUCAGUAAAUGUCUUUGUGACUGGCAAAUGGCAUAAAUUAUGUUUAAGAUUAUGAACUUUUCUGACAGUUGCAGCCAAUGUUUUCCCUACGAUACCAGAUUUCCAUCUUGGGGCAUAUUGGAUUGUUGUAUUUAAGACAGUCAGAAUAAUGAUAGUGUGUGGUCUCCAGAGGUAGUCAGAAUCCUGCUAUUGAGUUCUUUUUAUAUCUUCCUUUUCAAUUUUUUAUUACCAUUUUGUUUGUUUAGACUACACUUUGUAGGGAUUGAGGGGCAAAUUAUCUCUUGGAGUGGAAUUCCUGUGUUUUGAGCCUUACAACCAGGAAAUAUGAGCUAUACUAGAUAGCCUCAUGAUAGCAUUUACGAUAAGAACUUAUCUCGUGUGUUCAUGUAAUUUUUUGAGUAGGAACUGUUUUAUCUUGAAUAUUGUAGCUAACUAUAUAUAGCAGAACUGCCUCAGUCUUUUUAAGAAGGAAAUAAAUAAUAUAUGUGUAUGAAUUUAUAUAUACAUAUACACUCAUAGACAAACUUAACAGUUGGGGUCAUUCUAACAGUUAAAACAAUUGUUCCAUUGUUUAAAUCUCAGAUCCUGGUAAAAUGUUCUUAAUUUGUCUGUGUACAUUUUCCUUUCAUGGACAGACCAUUGGAGUACAUUAAUUUUCUUAAUCUGCCAUUUGGCAGUUCAUUUAAUAUACCAUUUUUUGGCAACUUGGUAACUAAGAAUCACAGCCAAAAUUUGUUAACAUCAAAGAAAGCUCUGCCAUAUACCCCGUUACUAAAUUAUUAUACAUCCAGCAGAUUCUGGGAUGUACUAACUUAGGGUUAACUUUGUUGUUGUUGAUAAUACUAGAUUGCUCCCUCUUUAAUUCUUCUUCUGGUGCAAGGUUGCUGCUUAAGUUACCCUGGGAAAUACUACUACAAGGUCAAAUUUUCUAGUAUCUUACAGCCUGAUUGAAGGUGAUUCAGAUCUUUGCUCAAUAUAAAUGGAUUUUCCAAGAUUCUCUGGGCCAUCCUUGACCCACAGGUGAUCUCGCUGGAGUAUAUUAACUUAACUUCAGUGCCAGUUGGUUUGGUGCCAUGAGAUCCAUAAUGAAUCCAGAACUUCACCAUUGCUUAGAUAUAAGAGUCCCUUGGAAGAAUAAUGCCACUGAUGAUGGGGGUCAGAAGGUGUAUUAACUCAACAUAGAGGGCUUUUAGAUUUUUCUUCAAAAAAAUUUCGAGAAAAGUAUUCUUUUACCCUCCAAACAGUUAACAGCUCUUAGUUUCUCCAAAUAUGCUCUUUGAUUUACUUAUUUUUAAUUAAAGAUGGUAAUUUAUUGAACAAUGAAAUCCGUAAUAUAUUGAUUUAAGGACAAAAGUGAAGUUUUAGAAUUAUAAAAGUACUUAAAUAUUAUAUAUUUUCCAUUUCAUAAUUGUUUUCCUUUCUCUGUGGCUUUAAAGUUUUUGACUAUUUUACAAUGUUAAUCACUAGGUAACUUGCCAUAUUUCUGGUUCUAUAUUAAGUUCUAUCCUUUAUAAUGCUGUUAUUAUAAAGCUGGUUUUUAGCAUUUGUCUGUAGCAAUAGAAAUUUUACUAAGUCUCUGUUCUCCCAGUAAGUUUUUUCUUUUCUCAGUAAGUCCCUAAGAAAACAUUUGUUUGCCACUCUUACUAUUCCCAAUCUUGGAUUGUUCGAGCUGAAAAAAAAUUUGAUGAGAAACAGGAGGAUCCUUUUCUGGUGAAUAUAGGUUCCUGCUUUAAGAAUGUGGAAAUCCAUUGCUUUAUAUAACUAAUAUACACACAGAUUAAUUAAAAUUGUGAGAAAUAAUUCACACAUGACAAGUAGGUAACAUGCAUGAGUUUUGAAUUUUUUUAAAAACCCAACUGUUUGACAAAAUAUAGAACCCAAAUUGGUACUUUCUUAGACCAGUGUAACCUCACACCUCAGUUUUGCUUUUCCAACCCUGACUUGAAAGGCAUAUUUGUAUCUUUUUAUUAGUGAUAGUGAAGCUGUGACACUAACCUUUUAUACAAAAGAGUAAAGAAAGAAAAACUACAGCGAUUAAGAUGAGAACAGUUCUGCAGUUGUUGAACUAGAUCACAGCAUUGUAGGCAGAAUAAAAAAUGUUCAUAUCUGAGAAUAUUCCUUUCGCCAUCUUUUCCCAAGGCCAGACCUCCUGGUGGAGCACAGUUAAAAGUAACAUUCUGGGCCUUUGUAAUCGGAGGGCUGUGUCUCCAGCUGGCAGCCUUUGUUUUAAUAUAUAAUGCAGGACUGUGGAAAACAGUUGGCAUAGAAUAUUUUCACCUAAAAAAGAAAGAAAAGACAUACAAAACUGGAUUAAUUGCAAAAAGAGAAUACAGUAAAAUACCAUAUAACUGGACAAAGCUAGAAGAACCUUUAGAAGAUUUGUCUGAAAACAGAUUUCAAGAGUGAGCUUUUAUACACUGCUCACUAAUUUGCUUGAUUACUACCAACUCUUCUUAAAGUUAACACGUUUAAGGUAUUUCUGGACUUCCUAGCCUUUUAGCAAGCUUAGAGGAACUAGCCAUUAGCUAGUGAUGUAAAAAUAUUUUGGGGACUGAUGCCCUUAAAGGUUAUGCCCUUGAAAGUUCUUACCUUUUCUCUAGUGAUAUUAAGGAACGAGUGGGUAGUGUUCUCAGGGUGACCAGCUGCCCUAAAGUGCCUGGGAUUGAGGGUUUCCCUGGAUGCGGGACUUUCCCUGGAUACAAAACUUUUAGCAGAGUUUUGUAUAUAUGUGGAUUUUUCUGAUAAGUAGCACAUCAGAGGCCUUAACCACUGCCCAAAAGCGAUUCUCCAUUGAGAGUACAUAUCUUGAACUUAAGAAAUUCAUUUGCUCUGAUUUUUAAUCUUGUAAAGUUUUUGCUAAACUCAAAACAAGUCCCAGGCACACCAGAAGGAGCUGACCACCUUAGGUGUUCUUGUGAUUUAUCCUUACUUCCCUAUGUUGUCAUAGUUGCUUCUAAACUCAGCUGCACUAUGGCUGUCAACAUUUCUGAUACUUAUUGGGAUAUGUGCCAUCCAGUCAUUUAGUACUUUGAAUGGAACAUGAGAUUUAUAACACAGGUAAUAGCUGAAGGUACCAGUAUGGUGGUGAGACUCACACUUAGUGAUCCAGCUAAGGUAACUGAUGUUAUAAUGGAACAGAGAAGAGGCCAACUAGAUAGCUAAGUUCUUCUGAACCUAUGUGUAUAUGUAAGUACAAAUCAUGCGUCCUUAUGGGGUUAAACUUAAUCUGAAAUUUACAUUUUUCAUAGUAAAAGGAAACCAAUUGUUGCAGAUUUCUUUUCUUGUGAGGAAAUACAUGGCCUUUGAUGCUCUGGCGUCUACUGCAUUUCCCAGUCUGUUCUGCUCGAGAAGCCAGAAUGUGUUGUUAACAUUUUUCCGUGAAUGUUGUGUUAAAAUGAUUAAAUGCAUCAGCCAAUGGCAAGUGAAGGAAUUGGGUGUCCUGAUGCAGACUGAGCAGUUUCUCUCAAUUGUAGCCUCAUACUCAUAAGGUGCUUACCAGCUAGAACAUUGAGCACGUGAGGUGAGAUUUUUUUUCUCUGAUGGCAUUAACUUUGUAAUGCAAUAUGAUGGAUGCAGACCCUGUUCUUGUUUCCCUCUGGAAGUCCUUAGUGGCUGCAUCCUUGGUGCACUGUGAUGGAGAUAUUAAAUGUGUUCUUUGUGAGCUUUCGUUCUAUGAUUGUCAAAAGUACGAUGUGGUUCCUUUUUUAUUUUUAUUAAACAAUGAGCUGAGGCUUUAUUACAGCUGGUUUUCAAGUUAAAAUUGUUGAAUACUGAUGUCUUUCUCCCACCUACACCAAAUAUUUUAGUCUAUUUAAAGUACAAAAAAAGUUCUGCUUAAGAAAACAUUGCUUACAUGUCCUGUGAUUUCUGGUCAAUUUUUAUAUAUAUUUGUGUGCAUCAUCUGUAUGUGCUUUCACUUUUUACCUUGUUUGCUCUUACCUGUGUUAACAGCCCUGUCACCGUUGAAAGGUGGACAGUUUUCCUAGCAUUAAAAGAAAGCCAUUUGAGUUGUUUACCAUGUUACUAUGGGACUAAUUUUUAAUUGUUUUAAUUUUUAUUUAAACUGAUCUUUUUUUAUAUGGGAUUACAUUUUGGUGUUCACUCCCUAAAUUAUAUGGAAACCAAAAAAAGUGAUUGUAUUUCACAUAUGGACAUAUGAUUUUAAGAGUACAUGUUUUUGUUUUUUUAAUUUGGUGUUACAUAAAAGAUUAUCCUAUCCCCCCGGGAGAUAAAUUUAUACUACUUAAUAUAACCCCACAACAGGCGCACACCACACACUGCACAGUGCUAUUUAUACAUUUUUAUUUAUUUCAGAGUUUGCCUAUGCUACAUUAGCGCUCUAAUACAUAAGAUCUAUGCUGUAAACAAAAACAUCUUCAAAGUUGAAAUUUGCUGAAAUAUACUUUUAACAAAAUAACAUUUUUAAGGCUCCAUUGAAAAAUACUAGAUAAGAUAUAAUCUCAUAUAAUCAGUAUGAAUAAUUUUAAAAAUGAGAAAUAUUUAGGUCAGCCACACUUCCUUUGUGCCUUGCAAGAAUUCAGUUCUGUGGAUGAAUCAGUACUGGUUAGCAGACUGUUUUCUGCAAACCAUUUUAAACAUGCUUUAGUAUGCAACAAAAAGGGACCUCAAAUGCUAAAAUACACUAUUUUACGUGGCAUUGAAUAGCCUUGGGACUGGUGUAGUUUUAUCAACACUUUUUUAUUAGGAAGAAACCCAAGAAAAUUUACUGUAAUUGCUACCACCUGCCACUGUAUAAAUAAUCUAAAAGGGACUUCCCAACAUUGAACAACAACAUUGAGGGCUGACUCGAGAUCCUUCUACAUUGUCACCUCAGCCUGGCUUUGCCUGUCACUGCUUAGCUUGAAGUAGUGACACUGUUCUGUAUCAGGAGAUUUUUAUAAUGGCCCUAGCAUCCAUAAUUCCACAUGUUCAUCAAAUGGCUGAAGAGUAUGAGAGAAGUAUUAAGGUCUAUGUUUGGGCUGUCUCCCCACUUGGCAUAUUCUGUUUUUCCCUCUUCAAAAUAGAUUGAAAGCCUCUUAGUGCAGGAAGCAGGCAUCAGUAUCAAACUGAUGUCAUCCAAUGUAAUUAUUUUAAGCUCCAGGUUUGUCUAAGUUUGGGUGAAGAAUGUUCAGGAACAUGUUUGCAACAUACAGUUAUCCAGCUUACCCUUUGACAGAUUCACCCUUCUCAUCAAAAUAGUAAGCCCAACCUAAAAAUUAUAAGUUUACAAAUAAAGGAAUAGAAAAACCCAAAAAGCUAAUUUACACAUAAAAAUUAUCUUUUGCUGCAAUAAAUAGGUAUGGAAAUAUUUGUAGAAUUGGUUUAACUGAUUUUGUAAAACAAAUGUCAUGCUAUUUUGCCAUAGUGAGACAUGCAGUAAUUCUUAAAAUCACAUUAAUAGAAGGCAAGAACAUUGAAUCAGACUUAGCAGAUAACAGAUUCAGUGAUAAAUGAACAAUAGACUAAGCAUACUUAGGAAGCUACAUGAGAACAGAAUGUAUUACUGUGCUCCCGUCCAAACUGCAUGACUUUAUUGGUUAUAGAAUAAAUGGAAUUUGAGAUGGGGAUUUGCCAGUUUUUACAGUCUGUCUUCAAUAGUUUUGUUGGCUGCCUCUGCACCUUUCUAAAUGUUAUGUGAAAAUAAAAUUAUUUAAGUUCUAAAGUAGUUUAGGAAAGAGAUGUGAUGACAGGAAAAAGAAGUUAACUUCUGAACAGUUUGGUCCAGGAAGAAGAUGGGCAGAAUACAGUAAGCCCAGGGUUGAAGAAUACAUUCAAUUUGGAGAGAUGGAGAAGACCUUUGAAGAAGGUCAAAAUGAGAUCUUGGAACAGAACUCUCACCUGUGUGUCUGGAUAUACAUGAAAACUGGACGGUGUUAUUGAGCUACUGCUUAUAUGGUGAGCAGAAAAUUGAUAACCACAAGCCUGGUAGGUUCUGCUAUGAAGCCCACAUAUAAUCACAAGGCCUAGAUAGCUUGGAGUUAAAAGCCAAGGAUAGCUGUAUAGUUUGGGUUCCAUAGUUUGCAGUGAGAUUGUGCUUCUGAGCAGUCAUUUGGGGGCAGUGGUUCUGAGAUUACAAGCCAUAACCCAGCCAAGAACGGGCUACCUGUGGAAUGAGGAUGAGGAAGUUGCUACAUAUAAACCCUAGUGUGUGUGUGUGUAUUAAGUGAAACUUAGUUAACUUUUUUGCUCACAGCCAAAGAUGAUUCAUCUAGAGAAGCCAUUGGAAUUUUAGCAGAGUUUUGUAUAUAUGUGGAUUUUUCUAAUAAGUAGCAAAUCAGAGGCCUUAACCACUGCCCAACAGCGAUUCUCCAUUGAGAGUACGUAUCUUGAACUUAAGAAAUUCAUUUGCUCUGAUUUUAAAUCUUGUAAAGUUUUUCUUCAUGAGAGGUCUUGCCUCUAAACUAUAUUGUGGCAGUAUUUGAUCAAACUACAUAAGUACCAUGUAAAUAAGAUUUUAAUACAAAUGAUGACUCACUUCUAAAUGGUUUGCCAUUUAGAAAUGUGCUGCUGUGAGAAAAACGAAUUUUUUUUUUUUUUUUUUGGAGACAGAGUCUUGCUCUGUUGCCCAGGCUGGGGUGCAGUGGGGCGAUCUCGGCUCACUGCAGCCUCGCCUCCUGGGUUCAAGUGAUUCUCCUGCCUUAGCCUCCUGAGUAGCUGGGAUUACAGGCACACACCACCACGCCCAACUACUUUUUGUAUUUUUAGUGGAGACAGGGUUUCACCAUGUUUGCCAGGCUGGUCUUGAACUCCUGACCUCAGAUGAUUUGCCUGCCUCGGCCUCCCAAAGUGCUGGAAUUACAGGCGUGAGCCAUCAUGCCUGGCUGAAAAGUGAAAAUUUAAGCCAGCUUACCACCUGGAAUAAAAAUGUUUUAUAGGAAUGUCUAGGUUGCUCUUUUAUAUUGAAAAAAAACUUAUUAGUGUCUGUUUUACCCAAGAACCACAAGCUACUUCAUUUCAACUUUUAAAUCAUGAAUAAUAACGUGUUAUCACCACAUUUAAAAAUGUACAUCGUCAAUCACAAACACAUAUUCUAAGGAAUUGAAUUUUAUAGAGAUAAUUGAAUGCUUUCAUCUGUAAAAGAAUUAGUGGCCUGCAAACCACUGUGGAUUCUUGCUAUGCUUUGAAGUUGUCAGUGGGGGAAUUUGCUGCUGCAAGUUACUUAGACUUGUAGGCAAAGGGAAAUUCAAAUUUUUAAUUCUAAAAUGAAAACCACUGACAAAAUUUUAUACUCUGAAAGUUUGGUUGUUAGCUUAGUCAUUAUUUUCCUGUUCUUUAUCAUUUCGGAAUUCAGAUGCUUAAAUUUAACAUACAAAUUAUUUGUUGGUAAAACAUAAAACAUAAAAAGCUACAUUUGGUAAACUAAAUUUUAGGAUUCAAAGUCUCUAACAAUUUCUAUGUGACAUGUCAUACGGUGCAGUUUUUAUUUGCCAAAGUGUCUACUUCAUACUGCCUAUGCACUGCUUCCCGUUUUUAAUCUCUCUACCCCAACCCCCCUAUAAUUAAAUAAACCCCUAGAAAACUGCCUUCUUUUAGAAUACCUAAUUGAUUACUUUAAAUAUUUUUUCAGAAUCAAAAUUACAAAAGGGAGAGAUACCUAAGAAUCUGGCUUGUUUAUAUUCUUUAAAAGAUCGCAUUUGAUUGAAGGUGGGUGCAUAUUUUUUAUAUCCACUCUUUCCCCAUUUGUAUGUGACCAUUGUAAAAGUGGAUGUGCUUUUUUUUUUUUGCUGAGGUCUAGAGACAAUGUUUUAGAGAUACAGAAUGAAACAUUUAUGGGUAAAAUACAAUGGGUAAGACUUGCUUCAAAAUAGUAUGUGACAGAGGAAGUAGAUGGAGGUAUGAAUGAAUAGGACAUUGAUGGUUGUUUGUUGGGAUUGGGUAAGGGAGCUUUGUUGUAUUCUAUUUCCUUUUAGAUAAGUUUGAAAUUCCUUGUAGUGAAGAAAUUAAACGUCUCCAUCAGGUGCAUUGCCACGUCUUCUCUAGGAAGCCUCCUUAACAUCCUCUGGUGGCUCCUGAACUUUUUCUGUUCUCAUUCACAGGGAAGCUCAUGGGGCUGCCUGGAGACUUGAGGUUACAUCUUGCCUAGUAUUACCAAAAUUGUGAUACUUUUCUCCACCCCAUAAUAGCACAGUCUUUGGUCUCAACUUGAACUAAAGUCUUUUUUUUUUUUUUUUUUUUUUUUUUUAGUAUUUAUUGAUCAUUCUUGGGUGUUUCUCGGAGAGGGGGAUGUGGCAGGGUCAUAGGACAAUAGUGGAGGGAAGGUCAGCAGAUAAACAUGUGAACAAGGGUCUCUGGUUUUCCUAGGCAGAGGACCCUGCGGCCUUCUGCAGUGUUUGUGUCCCUGGGUACUUGAGAUUAAGGAGUGGUGAUGACUCUUAACGAGCAUGCUGCCUUCAAGCAUCUGUUUAACAAAGCACAUCUUGCACCGCCCUUAAUCCAUUUAACCCUGAGUGGACACAGCACAUGUUUCAGAGAGCACGGGGUUGGGGGUAAGGUUAUAGAUUAACAGCAUCCCAAGGCAGAAGAAUUUUUCCUAGUACAGAACAAAAUGGAGUCUCCUAUGUCUACUUCUUUCUACACAGACACAGCAACAAUCUGAUCUCUCUUUCCUUUCCCCACAUUUCCCCCUUUUCUAUUCGACAAAACCGCCAUCGUCAUCAUGGCCCGCUCUCAAUGAGCUGUUGGGUACACCUCCCAGACAGGGUGGCGGCCGGGCAGAGGGGCUCCUCACUUCCCAGACGGGGCGGCUGGGCAGAGGCGCCCCCCCACCUCCCGGACGGGGUGGAUGCUGGCCGGGGGCUGCCCCCCACCUCCCGAACGGGGCAGCUGGCCGGGCGGGGGUUGCCCCCCACCUCCCGGACGGGGCGGCUGGCCGAGCAGGGGCUGCCCCCCACCUCCCUCCCAGACGGGGCGGCUGCUGGGCGGAGACGCUCCUUACUUCCCGGACGGGGUGGUUGCUGGGCGGAGGGGCUCCUCACUUCUCAGACGGGGCGGCCGGGCAGAGACGCUCCUCACCUCCCAGACGGGGUGGCGGUCGGGCAGAGACACUCCUCACAUCCCAGACGGGGCGGCGGGGCAGAGGCGCUCCCCACAUCUCAGACGAUGGGCGGCCGGGAAGAGGCGCUCCUCACUUCCCAGACUGGGCGGCCGGGCUGAGGGGCUCCUCACAUCCCAGACGAUGGGCAGCCAGGCAGAGAUGCUCCUCACUUCCCAGACGGGGUGGCGGCCGGGCAGAGGCUGCAAUCUCCGCACUUUGGGAGGCCAAGGCAGGCGGCUGGGAGGUGGAGGUUGUAGCGAGCCGAGAUCGUGCCACUGCACUCCAGCCUGGGCAACAUUGAGCACUGAGUGAGCGAGACUCCAUCUGCAAUCCCAGCACCUCGGGAGGCCCAGGCGGGCAGAUCAUGCGCGGUCAGGAGCUGGAGACCAGCCUGGCCAACACGGCGAAACCCCGUCUCCACCAAAAAAUACAAAAACCAGUCAGGCGUGGCGGCGCGCGUCUGCAAUCCCAGGCACUCGGCAGGCUGAGGCAGGAGAAUCAGGCAGGGAGGUUGCAGUGAGCCGAGAUGGCGGCAGUACAGUCCAGCCUUGGCUCGGCAUCAGAGGGAGACGGUGGAAAGUGGGAGACCGUAGAAAGUGGGAGACGGGGGGAGACGGGAGAGGGAGAGGGAUGUGCUUUUUUUCUAACCGUUAUUGCCACCAAGUAAUAAUGUCUUAAUUCACAAUUUACAUAGUGAUUGGCUGGAGAGAGGUAUUGAGCAUAAAUUUUUUUUUAAGAUUCAACUGGGAAAUGGAUGAUUUACAUGAUUUUAGUCUCUUUAGUUGUCUGGGUAUUUCUUGACUGGGAAUAGCAAUAUCUUAAAGGCCAUUUUUAACAAGAAUGCUAAGGAUGGAACACUUGAAGGAAGCAGUCCUGUACAGUCAAAUACUUCAGUUACCUUGGAUAAUAGAAUGAAAACUCAAUUGCCUACUUUGAACAAAUUUUUUUUUUGGAUUUUAAUGGCUGGACAGAAUAACAUUCUGCUAAUUUUAAUCCUUGGUCAUUUCCGAUGUAAUGGAAAAUGCAGUUUGACUCAGAAUCGGAGGCCUGGGGUUUGGACCCUGAUUGUGCCAAUUUAUGUGACUUUAGAUAAAUCUUUUCAUCAGUCUACCUUAAAGUUCUUCAUUUCCUCCAGUUCCCUAAAAUGAGGAAGUUAGUUUUUAGGGUGGUUAUGAGAACUAAAUGAGAGCACUUGAGAGAUCAUUCAGCCUGAAGUGGGUACUCAGUAUUAGAUGGCUAAAUCUGCACAGUCUAGAAUACCAGGCAAAGGUUACUCUGAAGGUCUUUGCUAAUAACAAAUCUUUCUCUAAGAAAGUUUGUAAAUGUGAUGUUAAACUCAGAAAUGUCACAUAGAACAUAUUGGAGCAAUUAUUGCCGCAAAAGUAACUCGUAGCAACCACAAAAACCCAGUGGUGUGCAGCAAUAAACAGUUUAUGAAUUAGAUAAGUGAUUUCGGCUAGAUGUCUCUGGAGCAGUUGUAGUCUUUCCUCGUUCAUGAGGGAGUUGGCCUCACCUGGAAGGACUUGGCAUUUUUCCACAUGCCUCCUAUCCUCCAUUAAACAAGCAUGUUUUUGUGGAGGUUGUAGAAGGCAACAACAGCCAAGCCCAAUCCCAUAACUCCCUUUCAUGUCUGCAUGCUUCAUGCUAACUAGCAUUCACCAGAAACAAGCCACAUGGCUAAACCCAGUGUGGAAAGGCACUACAGAGUUAUUAGACCAAGGGAGAGAACAUAGGAGGGGUGAAGAAUUGGAGCCUUAAAUGCAGUCAAUCUACCACACCCUUGCUUUGUAUUUAACAGGUUACUGUACUGGUUUGCCAGCAAACAAUGGAAAAUGUGGAGAAGCUGAAGAAUGCUCAAGCUGGGACUUAAUAGAGUGGCCUAUUUGGUUUGAAAUGUUUUAACUUACAGAGCAUUGAGUAGAAGCCUAAUCUAAUAUACAUAAGGAAGACAAAAGCAAAGGAUUGUGUUUUCUAUCUAAAGGUUAAUCAUUGUGGUUGCUCCUGGCCAUUAUCACAUGACUGGAAGUUAACACUCUCCAAACGCUGAGCCUAUCCUGUACAGCACUAGAAAGUAGAAAGAAUCACUCAAUUCAGGGAAACCGUUUUCUCUUAAUGUGAACAUUUACAUUAAUGCCAUUUCCAAAACCUUUCUGGGACUUCUUAAAUGCAAAGAUGCUAUCUGCUUUACUUCAUGCUGCCUGUUUUUAGGAGCUUGGAGUGCUUUAGGAAGCUUCCCAAUACUGGUUUAGCAGUAAUUUGGUUGACUGAUCAAGGCAUGUUUUAACUUUGACACUGAAAUUUUAAAAAGACAACAGUUAUCUUGCCCGGAGAGUCAAGUUUCUGCUUCCAAGGAGGUCAGGAAUUGUUCUCUUUGGUGAUGUGGCUGUGCUUGGUAGCCCUUGAAAGUGGAGUCGACAGCAGUCCUCAGCUUUUGUGUGCCUGUCUUAGUCUGUUUUGUGUUACUAUAACAGGAUAGCUGAGGCAGGGUCACUUAUGAAGGAUGCUCACAGUUCUACAGGCUGGGAAGUUCAAGGGCAUGGCCCUGGCUUUUGGCAAGGGCUUUGCUGCUGCUUCAUAGCUUGAUGGAGAAGGUCAGAGGGGAAGCAGACGUGCAAACAACCCACUUGUUCACAACAACCAAACAAGUCUCUUUUUAACAACCCACUCCUGGGGACUAAUCUAGUCUUGAGAGAGUGAGAACUCAUUGCAAGAGCAGCACCAAGCCAUUCAUGAAGCAUCUGCCUCAGUGAACCAAACAUCUCCCACUAGGCCCCAGCUCUCAACACCACCACAAUGAAGAUAAAAUCUCAUCAUACAUUUGAGGGACAGUUUGGGAGACAGACCAUAGCAGUGCUCAGUAUUUCUACCCAAAUGUUCAGGUAACUUAAUAUAUUUUUCCUUGAAUAUAUGUUUAAAUGGGCUUCCCUUCCCCACGCUCAUCUUGAAUGGUCCCACAACAACUUUUGAUUAUCACGUUCCUGUAAAUACACAAAAAUAUUUUGUGGUCUUUUACUGGCAGCCCAGUGGAUGGGACUUUAAAAAAUCACCCAGAUUCCAACAACCAGAGAAAACGACUGGUGUAUAUUUUUUCCAGUCUUUAUUUGUAUGUCUGUGUAUAUUCAAUGGAAAAUGUUUGAAGCUUCACUCACAGCACAUUCCAUUAGAGAAAGCUACUAAAAUCAUAAGGAAAAUCUAAAAUGCAGUAAGCCAGUCAGCAAGCCAUAAUGGGCAUAUGAAAACAAAGUUUUUUGCCAUGAUUUGUGGACCACAGAAGAUCUGUGUUAUUAGUCUAUUUAAGUUUGGUGUUUGAAAUUAAAAAUGUUCGACAUACUUUUUAUGUUUUUUUUAAAUAUACUGUCUAUAUUUAAAAUUGAGUAUACUGUACUUUAGUGUGUUUGGAAGCAGAUAUCCCCAAAUAAAAGUAUACAGUAGAACCAAAGAAUUUUAUUGAUCAGCUAGAAUUUAGUUUUCAGGUGUAAUAACUGUCAACCUAAAUAACAGAGGCUUUCUAAAAGAAAAUGAUGUUUAUUUGGGAAUAGGGCAUUGUGAAGGCAAUAUGCAUGCCAUAGUAAACUGUGUGUAUUCAGGAAGGUAAAGGAAGACAGGUUUUUAAAGGACAGAUAAAGAUUAUAUAAUUGUCUUGAAAUAAUUAUUCUUGGCUACAAGGAUUAAUAACAAGGAUGCUGCCAGUUCGGGUUUGGACAAUCGGCUUCUAGGCAGAUGUCCCAAAAGUAUUUUCUGUGUAAGGUUGCGAAUAGUGUUUGUGCAAGCUGGCGUGGUUUCUUCUGGGUCUUUGAGGUAGUGCGUAAAAUCCCUCUCUUCAUGGACUUCCCUGGCUCCAUUUGUCAGGGCUUUUGGAAACAUGACUCUUGAUUCUGACAGCUUUCACCUUUCCCUCUCUUGAUGAAGAUGUUUUUCCGAAAGUAUCUAUGAUGAAUCAUCUUGUAGUUAGGCUUUGAUUGUCCCUUGGUGACAGAAUAGACCUUUCCCGGGUUAUUGGUCUGGUCCUGCAUCCUGCAUUGGCAGGAGUGAUUGGCAACUAAAAGUCAGUGUUAAAACCCUUUUAGCCACCUUUGAGGGCAGGGAGGCUUUAAGGGAGUGGCACUUAGGCUAAGUCCACCUGGAGUCUAUUAUUAAGUCCAAUUUUUUUUCCUUAGUCCUUUGUUGUCCCCUCAAAGUGCUGGGCUAGCAUUAUUCUGUUAGGAAUUGUACUUCUUUCUGCAGAAAAUUUGGCAAAUAACAGAUACAAAGUUUAAAAAGGAAAUACACAAAAUUAAUAGUAAUGUGACAAUCCCAGUUUGCAUAAUGGUUUUGAGCCCUGAACCUAGGCUUACAGGCAACCAAUUGAAUAAAUCAAAUUGUAAUACAAUUCUUGCUCUGAUGUCUUAGGAAAAAUGUCUACAGCCUGAAAUCAUCAACUUUUUGUCCUGGUUUGCAGUUUGAAUGUCUCUAGCUAUGGCAUUGGUUGGUAUGGUGAACUUUUGUGUGACCCAUACAUCAGCAUGAGACUUGCUCCUUUAAAAAUUAAUCACAUCUUAGCUUAUAGGCCUCAGAGCAUGGGAGUAGUUUUUUUUCUUAGAGAGUCAUAGCCAAAUAUUGAAGGAAAUUAGGAGGAUUCAGGAGCAAAUCCAGUCUGCAGGUGGAUAACAGGAGUUUCAAAACGGUACAGAGCUGUGAUCUAAUAACAGGUACAUAUAGCUUUCUUCAGAAACUUAAAGUUACCCUGAUUUUUACCAAAGAUGUUCAGAAUAAAACAGAUUUGUAAACUUUAUCAGAUUUUGUCUGCAAGAAUAGUAGUAUGGUCACAGUAAUCUCAGAUUUAAAAACCUCCUUGAGGCUAAGAAGCUAAGUCAAGGUAGACUUUAGAUUUUACCUAUAGUUUUAAGGUUCCUGGGCCUGCCAGGAAAUGAUAAUUUUUAAUUCAGUGUAAUGCUGAGAACCAUUGAAGCCAGGCAUUCUACACAUUCUCAAAUAUGACAUUUUAAUCAAAGCCUUGGUAAUACAACCAGUGUUUCCAAUUGUAUCCUGUUAUAACGAGAGCCGAUUUUUAUUGAACUUAGGCAAAUCAUAUUGCCUUAAGAGUACUCACAAAUAGGCUGGGCACAGUGGCUCAUGCCUGUAAUCCCAGCUCUUUGGGAGGCCAAGACAGGUGGAACACCUGAGGUCAGGAGUUUGAAACCAGCCUGGCCAACAUAGUGAAACCUCCCCCCGGCCACCGUCUCUACUAAAAAAUACAAAAAUUAGCUGGGUGUGGUGGUGCAUGCCUGUAGUCCCAGCUACUUGGGAGGCUGAGACAGAAUUGCUUGAACCCUGGAGGCAGAAGUUGCACUGAAACAAGAUCGUGCCACUGCAUUCCAGCUGGGGCAACAGAGCGAGACUCCGUCUCAAAAACAAAAACAAAUGAAUACUCAAAAUAGUUUCCAAAUUGGAGGGAUCAAGAAGAAAGGAAAAGCAAAUAUUUCUACCUUUGUUCACAAAAGUAUUCCAAAUUGCUGUAAACUAUAGAUAGCAUGAGAGAAUUUCUUUAAAUAUGGAAAACAAAACAUUUAAGUAAAAAAACAAUAAUGCUUCAAAUAAAAGUCACAGACACAUCUUCAGUUACUUAGUCUCAUGUAACUUUUUUUGUUGUGGUUGAUCUUAAUUAGUAGUUACAUGGACUCAUCAGUUUCUUGAAGUUCUGAAAAAAUAUUUAGUCCAUUGGUAUUAAAGUGAUUAGUAACCUGUAUUUAAAAGUGUGUUAGCAUCUUUUCCAUGAAUCUGAUUGCAAAUGCUUUUAGAGAAAAAGCAAUAACUGGGAAUUACAAAAACUUAGAAUAACCAUGAUUAAAAAUCUGAUGAGAGUUUACCAUAACCAGAAAUAGACAAAGAGUUUUGGUUAUUUUUGUGGCAAACAGCAUAAUCAGAAUUAUGACUGAUGACAUAUUUCUAACGGCAUCGUACAAUUUUGGAACACUCAUAUCAAUAACAUACUCAUAAAUGUAACUGUGUCUAGUAUUACAUCAUUAGACAAUGCUUUUCAUACAAUUUAAUACAUCAAAGAAGCCUAAUUAGCUAACAUCUCUACCAGAUGGCAUACACAUGCUCUGAGGCUUUCCAGAGGCCCAAGUGGAAAACUCAAAGGUAAUUUUAAGUCAAAAACACUUAAUUUAGAACUUGAGCCUAGAGAAGCCUGUCAAAGAUGUCAAAAGUUCGAAACAGGAUCACAGGUCACUAUAAAAUAUUUAACAAGAAUGAUAAUCAAAAGACUUAAGAAGCAAUGCAGAAAGUUACAUACAUUUAAAAACCAUCUUUUCAAAGCUUCAUUUUUCCCAAGCAAAAAAAAAACUUAAACACAAGAAUUUAUCUUGAUAGAACAUAAAAUUUUUCUUAGGCCAGUUGCCAAAAUGGUAAAGAAAAAUCUCUUGCAGUGUGACUGCCUUUACUUAUGGGAAGCCUAUUUGGAUAUACUGAAAGUUGAAUCUGAUGAAAAGGUACUUGAAUUUAAUCAGACACAGGAAGAGUAUUUCCAAGGUUAUGAGUGUACGCCUUAUAGAGGAAUGUAAAUAAGAAAGCUAGUAUGUUGAACAGAAUACAUGGCUCUUGGAAAAAUUACGAGAAAUUUCCUGCUUGCGUGGAACAAUUCAAACAUGAGAAGAGCCAAGAAUUCAGAAUCAAGUUAUACUGGAGGAAAACAUUGCUUUUCUAGGCCUUCUACAGAACAUUUCAGUAUCAAGUUAUAACAGCAAGAGUUAGAACCAGAGGAAAAAAGUUACAGGAGCUAAUGAAAAAGUUAAGAGUUAUCACCCCUGCCAAACAAAAAGAUGUACCUUCUUAAGGGGAGAAAGAGCUAAAGGCAAUGAUGUGUGACCUACAAAUAAGGUGCAGCAAGAUACAGCAAAGGUUGAACUUGUGAGAUAUAAAUCAGGAUCUUCAAGAAGAAAACUCUACCUCAAGAAAUGAAAUGACCAUCUUAAAUGAAAAAAGACAGCCUUUCUAACCUGAAUCUAGGGGAAAUUAAACGGAUCUCAGAAGGAAAUAUGGCAGAAAUUUAAACUGUGGUUUAGAAGAUGGCUGAUUUUAGAAUUAAAAAUUAAAACCUCUUUCAAUUUUAUUAAGACCAGAUCCUUAAAAAGAACCUUGUUCUAACAUUGGGGACCAAAUUUUGUGUGUGUGUGUGUGUGUGUGUGUGUGUGUGUGUGUGUGUGUGUAUAGUGCAUGUAUAGCAUUUACACUAUCGUGUAUAUACAAAUAUAUAGCAUAUGUAUAGAAUAUACUGUAUUAUUGUACAUAUACAUAUGUACAAGUAUAUAUGUAAGCUCAAUGUCUUAUGAUUUCAUUCUGACCUAUUGCCAACUUCAUUACACACAACUCCUUUCAUAAAUGUAUCCUUCAUGAACAUUUCAUGAUCUGCACAGACCUUCAGUGACAUGCUUAAACUUUCUGCUUUGUUUUAUACUUCCCCUUAAACAACUGGUCAUCCUGCUUUAGGAUAAAAAGUUACUAUGCAAGACUCAUACAGAAUUAUUCUGUUAAUUUUGUAACCUUCCUUACCAAAGGUACAUUCUCACACCCAUUAACUUCCUUCAUAUUUCUCUCCUCCUCCUACUUAGUGGUUCCUUUCUGUCUUGUUUCCAUAUUUGAAACAACCUCUAAUAAACUCUGAAUUUAAACAACUUUUUUCCCAAUAAAAAGCAAUUUUUAUGCCUUAUAACUUUUCUCAUCAAAACAUCUUUUUUUGGGUACACUUUGUAUAUGGAAUUGUGUAUUUUCAAAUUUUAACUUAUUAACCUUAAUUUUUAGUGAAAACCUAGGAAGCAAAAUUUUGAAGUGUUAUAUCAGCAUUUUAUAAAUGAGAACCAUAUUAUAAUUUUUAGAAACAUGUUUCCUUAUAACUUUGUAUAUUAAUAGGCCCAAAUAUAUUUAGUCUUUCUAUAAUUUAGGAAGCCAAGAACAAACUAAUAUUUUCAGCAGUUUAUUGUUUUUUUUUGGAAAUGAUCCAGACAUUUACUGAAGAUUAAUUUAUAAGAUUUCAAAUUACAUGAAAAGUUCAUUAACAUCCUAUUUUUAAAAACAUUCUUUUGGUUUAUUUUUUAGAGACAAUGUCUUGCUGUGUUACCCAGGCUGGAGUUCAGUGGCUGUUCACAGGCACAAUUGUAGCACACUGCAGCCUCAAACUCCAACUCACACAAUCCUCCUGCCUCCGUUUCCUGAGUAGCUGGAACUAUAGAUGCAUACCUGCAUACCACCAUGUCUCACCCUUGCUUAUCCCGUUUAUAAUCCAUCCAAUUCUUUUUUUUUUUUUUUUUUUUGAGACGGAGUCUCGCUCUGUCACCCAGGCUGGAGUGCAGUGGCGUGAUCUCGGCUCACUGCAAGCUCCGCCUUCUGGGUUCAUGCCAUUCUCCUGCCUCAGCCUCCCGAGUAGCUGGGACUACAGGCGCCCGCCACCGCGCCCAGCCAAUUUUUUGUAUUUUUAGUAGAGACGAGGUUUCACCGUGAUCUCGAUCUCCUGACCUCGUGAUCUGCCCGCCUUGGCCUCCCAAAGUGCUAGGAUUACAGGCGUGAGCCACUGCACCUGGCCCCCAAUUCAUUUUUAACAAUUAUUCCUAGAUUACUUAUAAAAACUGAGAUAUUAGACAUAGCUAGUCAUUUCAAGUUAUUUUCCUGUUAACCAUUUUUAUUACCUGUGAGUAUCAUGUGUUCAAUUAAGAACCAUAAAAAUGAAAUAUGUAGGUAUUUUGCCAGUAACUCAGAGGACACAGCUGAAGUCAAUAAUACAAAAUUAGUUCAACUUACAGUUAUACAAAGAUCAUUCUGUUUUUAAGUUGAGUUUAUAGUUUUAUGACCUUAAAAAGUCUAACAGAGACAAAUAUAAAACUGAGUAGUAAAUUCAGGCAAAAAUUUUAAAGACACUUAUUUUUGAUUUACCAAUUAUUUUAAAACCAGCUUAUCAGAUGUUUAAGUUAUAUUAACUAAAAGGCACUUGUGUUAAUUACUAUAUAUUUUGUAUUAGCACUCAUUUAUUUGAUGAAUAGAAUUCCUUAAGGGAUUUGUGGCCAACUGCCAGAUUUUACCACGUAGACACAACAUACAACAUAUAUAUACAUAUGUGUAAACACACCUAAACAUACACAUACACAAACAUAGCUUUCAUUUUAGAAUUUUAGUCAUACGAUAGUAAUACAGGCUUGCUGGUUUAUAAAAGACAGUUAUUGGAUUCAAAUUAUAUUUCUGAGAAAGUGGGACCUGCUCAGCUGGGUAAACAUGCAGAAUAGGUAAUCUUAUGAAAGCUGUGAACCAAAAGUUUUGGUAAAUAGCAGUUUGGAUUUUUAAAAAACCUCUUACCCCACCUCCCCAACCCCUUUUUUCCCUUUUUUCAGUUUCAAAUGAGUUUAAUGUUAAUAUUUAAAUGCUUACAUUUUUAGCUAGGACUGGCUGAAUUGUAUAAGAAAAAACAAUCUCCAGGUGGCCUUGAAUUUUUAGUAACAAAUCUUUUGUUUGCCAUUCUGGUUUUUUUGACUAGUCAGUGCAGGCAGGGAAGCAUUUUAGCAGUUGUGGAUGAGGGGUUUUUGUUUUGUUCUUUUAGCCUUUGCAUAGCAGGCAAGCAAUUUUUAUGCUAUACCAGAGAUACCUUAUAUUAUUGCCCUGAGCUCAAGAUUUUGACCUGUUUGAGAGCCUAAUUUUUAUACGUAUUUAUCUAGUUCUUUUAGGCUAUUAAUCCUUUAAUUAACUGUUCCAUCACCCUAAGCAGUUAUUAGGCAAACCUAAAUUUACAUUAAAAGGGAUACUUCUUAAUUCUAGGUGUUGGUUGCCAGGGAACUAUUAUAAUUUAUAAAGCCAUUAAUUUAAGGCCCUUUAAGACCUUUUUUUUUCUUUUUGUUCUUGGCUGGAAUGCCGUAAGGAGUGAGUUUCAUCUCAACACUGGCAGAAACAGCAGAUUUAAAGUAGGCAGAAAAAAAAUUAGAGAGCUUAGAAGACUCUACAUAUCAACUCUAUAGCUGCAGUCUCUUGGUACUAAGAAUAAAAAAGCUUGGGGAGUUUAGACAAAGCAUAGACAAUCUCUAUGAUGGUCAUUGAUCCAAAAACAUGCAUGAGGAAAAGCCACAUAGCUGACCUGAAGUCCCAGAAAAGCAGGCAUGCCUUAAUGUUUGAGAAUUUCCAUUUUGUUUCUUCUCAAUCUCUUAAGAGCAAAGAAAAUUCUGUAAAUCCUGACAGAUAAGUCAGGUGUUUGGACCAGUGUUUUAACUGGUGGCGAUUGCCCUAGUGGCUUUAAAAGAGCCAUCCUGUGCCCAAAAUUUAGAAUGUUUAUUUUUGCUCUUGGGAGAUGUUCAGAAACAGGGGAAAAGAGCCAAAUCAUUUACAGAUGCAUGUAACCAUAUCGAAACGAAACCAAAAUCAGUGUUCCCAAAAGUGUUAACCCAGUCAUGCAGAUUAAAAAAUAAUAUAAACACAGAAGAACCCAAAGUAAAUUUACCAGAAAAGGCAUGCCUCAGAAUCCAGAGUACUCAGCCAGGCGCAGUGGCCCAUGCCUGUAAUCCCAGCACUUUGGGAGGCCAAGGCAGGAGGAUCGCUUGAGCCCAUGAGUUCAAGACCAGCCUCAGCAGUAUAGUGAGACACUGUCUCUAAAAAAAAAUUGUUUUUAAAUCCAGAGUACUCAAACCAGAGGGACACUUGUCUUUAUAUCAAAAAGGACUUGCCAGGAAAGACAAAAAGUCUUUUGUCAUCCCAGGAGGGAUGUAAAGUCCUUUAUUAAAGUGGUCUUAGAACCAAGACAAAUCCAAAGUCAAGUCAAAAAGCCUCUGCCAAAAGUGGGAGGCUCUGCCUGAGAAAAGACUCACUGGGGCAGAACAGACAAGCUAUGUAAGCGGAGAGCCCAAAGGGCUCCUGUGAGUACUGCAUACUGAUUCUGAGAUCACCACUUCUCUCUGAAAUGUGUCCUACUUCAGGUUCUACUGCUGAACACCAUUUAUGUCAACACAGAGAGAGGCUCUCUAAAAGAAAACUCUAUUUGGGAAUACAGCAUUGCUGUAGAAAUACGCAUGUCAUGGGCCGUGCGCGGUGGCUUAUGCCUGUAAUCCCAGCACUUUGGGAGGCUGAGGUGGGCCGAUCACGAGGUCAGGAGUUUGAGACCAGCCUGGCCAACAUAGUGAAACCCCCUCUCUACUAAAAAUACAAAAAAUUAGAUGGGUGUAUUGGUGGGUGCCUAUGAUCCCGCUACUUGGGAGGCUGAGGCAGAAGAUUGGCUUGAACCUGAGAAGUGGAGGUUGCAGUGAGCCUAGAUGUGCCACUGCACUCCAGCCUGGGCGACAGUGCAAAACUACGUCUCCAAAAAAAAAAAAAAAAGACCCAUGUCAUGGUAAACUACGUGUGUAUUCAGGGAAGUAAAGGAAGACAAAGAUUUUAAAGAAAAAUGAGGGUUGUAUAAUUGUUUUGAAAUAAUUGUCGUUGGUUACAAAGAUCAAUAGCAAGGGUGGUGCCACUCUGAAGUUGGACAGGCAGUGGCUAGGCAAAAGUAUUUUGUGGGUAACCUUUGUGAAAGGUUGCAGUUUUUGUAACACAAGCUGCUUUAUUUUCCCAAAAGCUUUCACAGUACAUAGAAAAUAUAUUGGACGUGUAUUAAAUGUGCCAAAUUAGUCAGCAAUAUUACAUUAAAAUAUGUGUUAUUACUUGUUAAUGUUCUUAAUAAGUUGUUCAGGCAGUUAUACCAGACUAUCUUUUCUCAUUUUCCAAUUUAUAAGUGUAUUAUCCAAAAAUGUUAGUUUUAGGGUGACCACUGUAUAUUUUGGUAUUUUUUAAAGCUACCCAAUUGUGUAUAAUUUAUAAAAAUCUUUUUUUCAUAAGACCUAAAACUUCUGAACAAUACAUAGGUGCAAAUAAAUAAAUUCCUUUUUAUCUCAAACUCACUUCCACUGCCCUCCCUGAAGAAAGCCUUUUGUUAUUGUUGUCUUGACUAAAUGUGGCAUGGGAGCUAACAUUUUCAAGGGAAGCUGAUCUUAUCUCCGGGCUCUAGAAGCCAAGACAUGAGGUAUGUGUUUACCGUCUCUUAGGUGACUCUCCAGAACUUUCAUUCUCAACCUCCUCCCUCACUGCCAGUUCCUCCUCAGCUUCUUAGCCAAGUGGUAGAGGAAAAAUGGUAUUUUAUGUCAGGACUAAGCCAUGUGCUCUGAGCCCUGGGUAAGUCUGCAAGGCUUCUCUAGAACUCAUACAUAGGUCAAUUAUUCCUCCUCUGAAAACUUAAACUCUGGCACCACUAGCUUUUUCCUACAGCAUACAUGGGCUCAGUAAAUCCUCUGUUAAGACAACAGGAAAAUUAAGACAAUGUCCUUGCAAGCCCCAUAACUACUUUCUAUCCCUGCUAUUCACAGCCAAGUGUGUCGAGACCAGUUCACACAAACCUUGUUGAUUUUCGGUUUCACCCCCUCCUUACUAAAUCACCCCUCCAUUUGCUGCAGUUGCCCUUGCGUGCUGUACUCAGACUUGGAGGAAGUGAUGUCUUAUUCAAGGCCAGUUUUUGUACUAGUGGUUAAAUAAAUGGUUUCCAAAUUGGAGUCAGAAGGAGAGCUUCUAAAAUGUAGGUUCCCUGGCCUCAAUUGUGAGAUUCUGCUUUAGCAGGUCUGGAAUUGGAGCACUGGGAUCUGCAUUUUCAGAAAACCCAAAAUGAUUAUCAGCCAGGACUUAAACCUCUGCUUUAGACCACAUUCCCUGUGGGCUUUCAGAUUUUCUAUCAAUGUUCUUCCCUCUUCCCAGCUCCCACACAUUAAAACUCAGAUCAUGCAGAAAAGAAGUUACAGUUCCUUCAUUUCACAUCAAUUUCUCAUGCAUCCCAUCUGGUUUUGGGAAGGUGUGGGACGAGGUGGAUGGCCUUAAACUUGCCAAUCAAAGAUAACGUUCUCUUUCGAUUCAAAUAGCCUAUCUCAGGCUUAAAACCAUCUCUUUGGAUAAAUGCUCAGCUUUUCAAAGGUUCUUCCUAGCUUCUUCCUCAUGAUGGCAUCUAGUGGGUGAGAACAGUCAUCUCCAGGUGACACAGGAAAGAGUUUCUCUAAUGUAUGUGCUGAGGUCCUUGACGGUCCUGCUGCUGGUGCUCAUCCUGCCAUCUUUGCUGGAUGUCACUGAGUCUACUGGGUAAUGUAAGUGGGUCCCUGGCUUUUGUUCACUGCUGUCAUGCCCUGCUCCUGACCACAACUCUGUCAUUGCCUUUGGUCUCAAGGUCUCUACCUUAAUAGCUUCCAUGUCCCAACUAUGGGACUGUUAAUCUGCUGGGCUUUGGAGUGGGUGGGAAGGGAUGAUGUUGGAACUUUGGGAUGUACUGAACAUCUUGCUCAAGCUUUGGGAAGCCAACAUUUUCUCAGACUGACUAGACACCUCCUUCCACCAAUGCUGAGCUAGUGCUCCUGUGCCAUACUGGGUAAGCCUCUAAGUCAUGAGUAGGACUUUUUUGAGUGGCUUGCAGUCUUCCCCAGGCUAUGCCAGGAAAGUAGUUGACUAACCCUGCUGCUCCAAGACUCGCAUACCCAUCCUGAAGUUUCCGUUUAUUUCCCAACAGGGCAAUUGCAAUCUCAAUCAAUCUCUCCCUGCCCUGGGAGUCAUUCCACUCCUGCCUAAUGAAGAGACUCUUCUCACAUCGUAUUCUCAGUUUCUCUUAUCCAUGGUUAGGAGUAAAACUCAUGUUCAGUUGUCCAAGCUUUGCUUUUAGUAUGUGAAUGGAGCUCUUAGCAUGUAGAACUCCCUUCUCAUUCUCAGUAAAGUCUGACUUUGAAGACUACUUAUCAUCUUCCUAGAGAUGCCAAAGAAUAAUCAAGAUAAUAAAGGCAGGCUCUGAGAUUCACAGCUGAGUAGCAACUGUGCUGUUACUCUAGUACACACCCUCUCCUUUCCUGUGACUGUCAGGCUUCAGGGCUUACCUUUAUUGGAAAGACAGCAGGGGGGCAUAUAUGAAGAAAAUGGAAUCUUUAAUAUUGUCAAAGUCUUGACCCAAUAGAGACAUUCUUGCCCCAGACUCUCUUGCUUCAGUGCCUUUGCCUGUUCUGGUCCUAAGUACCUUGAAUAUCCUUCUCUUGAUGCCCUGAUAUAAAACUCUUUAUUCCUCAAAGCCAAGUUCAGGUUAUCACCUCCACCACAGACUUUUCUUUCCCUCCCCAAACUUCAUUGCCUCUUCUCAUCACUCCCUUUGUAAUUUGUUUAUACUGGUAAGAGAGCAUUCAUCAUAAUUAGGCCUAUCUAUGCCUACCUUUCUUGUUAAAUUAUGAGCUUUGUUCUGCCUUGGAUAUCUCUCUGGCUUGGAUAUCUCUCUGGCCUUUGCUCUGCACUUCCAAAUGUAUCCAUUAUUCAAGACCCAGGUUUCCAGCCUGAUCAACAUAGCAAGAUCCCAUCUCUCCAAAAAAAAAAAAAAAAAAAAAUUGUGGGGCCGGGUACAGUGGCUCAUGCCUGUAAUCCCAGCACUUUGGGAGGCCGAGGCAGGUGGAUCAUGAGGUCACGAGUUUGAGACCAGUCUGGCCAACAUAGUGAAACCCCAUCUGUACUAAAAAUGCAGAAAAUUAGCCGGGUGUGGUGGUGUGUGCCUGUAAUCCCAGCUACUCGGGAGGCUGAGGCAGGAGAAUCGCAUGAACCCGGGAGGCAGAGGUUGCAGUGAGCCGAGAUUGCGCCACUGCACUCCAGCCUGGGUGACAUUGCAAGACUCCAUCUCAAAAAAAAAAAAAAAAAAAAUUAGCUGGGCAUGGUGGCAGGCACCUGUAGUCCCAGCUACUUGAGAGGCUGAGGUGGGAGGAUUGCUUGAGCCCAGGAAGUCGAGGCUUCAUGAGCCAUGUUUGUGCUACUGCACUCUAGCCUGGAUGACAAAGUGAGAUCCUUUUCUAAAAAUAAGGACCCAGUUUAUUUUAUUUAGUUAUUUAGUUAUUUUUGAGACCAAGUUUCAUCACUCAGGCUGGAGUGCAAUGGCACAGUCUUGACUCACUGCAACCUCUGCCUCCUGGAUUCAAGCAAUUCUUCUGCCUCAGCCUCUUGAGUAGCUGGGAUUGCAGGUGCCCGCCACCACACCUGGCUAAUUUUUGUAUUUUUGGUAGAGACAGGGUUUCACUAUGUUGGCCAGGCUGGUCUCAAACUCCUGACCUCAGGUGAUCCACCUGCCUUGGUCUCCCAAACUGCUGGGAUUACAGGUGUGAGUCACCCUGCCUGGCCAGAACCCAGUUUAAAUUCCAUCCUCUCUGCAGAGUCUUCCUUAACCACCCCUAUUGAAAGUUACCCCUGCUUCCUACAAGAAGUGGUACUUGGAUGUUCAUGAGAUACCUGUGCAAGGCUCCUGUGGGGGUCCUGGGGAGACAGUGACAUGGACACUCAUGAAAGGAACCUUGGAAUAGCGAGUGUGUGUGCUAUAAAAUGUGCUUUAGAUUUGAUUACCACCACUUAAGUUAUGAGCUCUGAUAUGGUUUGGGUCUCCAUCCCCACCCAAAUCUCAUCUUGAAUUGUAAUCCCUACAUGUUGAGGGAAGGAAGUAAUUGUAUUAUGGGGGUGGUUCUCCCAUGCUGUUCUCAUGAUAGUGAAUUCUCACAGGAUCUGAUGGUUUUAUAAAUGGUAGUUUUUCCUGUACUUUCACACACUCACACUCUCUUCUGCCACCUUGUGAAGAAGGUGCCUGCUUCCCCUUCUGCCAUAAUUGUAAGUUUCCUGAGGCCUCCCCAGCUGUAUUAGUCUGAUCUCACGCGGCUAAUAAAGAGAUACCGGAGACUGGGUAAUUUAUAAAAGAGGUUUAAUUGACUCACAGUUUUACAUGGCUGGGGAGGCCUCACAAUUAUGGCAGAAGGUGAAGGGGGAGCAAGACACAUCUUACAUGGCAUCAGGCGAGAGAGCUUGUGUAGGGGAACUCCCCUUUAUAAAACCAUCAGAUCUCGUGAGACUUAUUCACUAUUACAAGAGCAGCACGGGAAAGACCCACCCCCAUGAUUCAGUUACCUCUCACUGGGUCCCUCACAUAAUAUGGGGAAUUAUGGGAGCUCCAAUUCAAGAUGAGAUUUGGGUGGGGACACAGCCAAACUAUAUCACCAGCCAUGUGGAACUGUUGAGUCAAUUAAACCUCUUUCCUUUAUAAAUUACCCAGUCUCAGGUAUUUCUUUAUAGCAGUGUGAGAACAGACUAAUACAAGCACCUUGAGGUCAGAGGCUAAAAUCACUUUUUCCCAAACAUUUCCUUUUUAUAUAUGCUACAUCUUUGUGUCUGCUUCAACAUUUCCAGCAGUGCUUUAUAUAUGGUAGGCAUGCAAUAAAUGCUUCUUGAUCGACUGACAGGUGCUCAGAAGAUCUAGGUUGGUUGAUUCUCUUGUGAUGCCAUCUUUUCCUGAGAGCUCAUUAAUUUUUAAGUUGUUUUCCUUGAAAUGCAUGGUAUGUUUCCUCCACCCUGCUCUUUGCCUUUCAUAGGGUUCCAUUUUGAUCAGCUGCUCUCAUUGUCUGUUUUGUGAUCAAAGGUUCUGAUGAACUUUGGAAUAUGUGUAUGUUUGGAGUGAGGAUGGGGUCUGGAGGAGAUGCAUGGUUGAGGACCAAUUCACCCAACCCAGCUUACAGAAGUAAAGCGGCCCCUUAGGAGCACUGAAGCAUUGCUGUGGAUUUCAGAAUUACCUUAUUUCUUUUUCUUUUUUUUUUUUUUUUUUUUGAGACGAGGUCUCGCUCUGUCGCCCAGGCUGGAGUGCAGUGGCACAAUCUCAGCUCACUGCAAGCUCCGCCUCCUGGGUUCACACCAUUCUCCUCCCUCAGCCUCCCCAGCAGCUGGGACUAUAGGUGCACGCCGCCACGCCUGGCUAAUUUUUGUAUUUUUAGUGGAGACAGGGUUUCACCGUGUUAGCCAGGAUGGUCUCAAUCUCCUGACCUUGUGAUCCACCCGCCUCAGCCUCCCAAAGUGCUGGGAUUACAGGCGUGAGCCACCGUGCCCAGCCAGCUUCUUUCAAAUCAGAGUAGGCCUUCCAGUGUGGCAGGCCAUAAGAUCUGAAGUUUUCACCCUGUUCCUGGAAGCCAAGUGGACAGCAACUAAUUUUUACUUUCUUUAUUGCACAUUUGGGGCUUGGGGGAUAGAGUCAGAUGUGUGUCAGUUGAAACUGUAGCUACUGCAUUCCACUCCUUGGGGGAUCGUAGUGCUCAUGCCAACAGAAAACUUCGAGGCUAAUAAUUACUGUCUUCAGAGUACAAGACAGGCACGGAAGUUGUUUUGGCAUAAGAAAACCACGAUUUGCAUCCCACAGUCUAAGGAAGACGAUGCUGAAUUCAGAAGAUGGUGCAAAAGUGUGACAGUUCAGCUGUGGCGGCUGUUGCUGAUGCAUGGGACUAUUUUAUUUACAUUUCCUUUCUUCUUUUUUAACAGAGACAGGAUCUUGCUGUGUUGCCCAGCCUGGUCUUAAACUCCUGGGCCCAAGUGAUCCUCCCACCUCAGCCUCCCAACGUGUUGGGAUUACAGGCAUGAGCCACCAUGCCUGGGCUUUAUUUAUAUUUCCAAGUCAAAUGUUAGUUGGUCAAUCAGUCUUUUUAAGCACCAAUUUUGUGCCUAGCCUUGUGGAAACUGUAGGAAAAAGAUACUUUUUAUUUGGGAGGACCUUGAUUUGCUGUCACAGGUGCCACUAAUGCCAAUUAUAAGGCAGUGUGGAAUCAGGUGAUUGAAAGCCCAGUCUGUAGCAUAAACUGCUGCAGGGUUCCAGUGGGGGCAAUUAAGGUGGGCAGGGAGGGUGGAUAGCAUUUGACUUUGACAGCAUAACCUGAGCAGAGGCACAGUGGGGAUGGUGAGUGUGCAGUGGGAGGAGGGAGAGAGGUAAGUGGUAGGGAAGAGGUGGGAAGGGGGCAAGGAGAAGGCUCAGGAGGUUUGGGGACAGGGAAAUGACUUGGUUGGCGACCUCUUACUUUCUUCUCGUGUGUGCAAUUUGGAAUUCACUUGGUUCUUAGUAUUUCUGGGUCAGAUGACUUCUUUGCAGUAUGAGAAACCAUUUCCCAGGCUGGCUACCUGGGCUGUGGUAUCUUCCAGUGCUCCUCUGUGAUUGUACUCAGAUCAGCUCGUCUAGGCAGGCAGGAUGGCAGAAGCCCUCUGACUUCAUGUCUGAAAGAGUAUGUGUUUCAACUCUGUAAUUACAGCAUUUAACAGACGAUAUCAGCCCUCUUUGGGAUGGCUUUUGGCAAAUGGGCUAGAAGUCUAUUGUGCAUUUAAAUGAUACUGCAUCUUCUCUUUAAAAGGUUUCUCAGUGAGUCCACCCCACUCUGUAUCCAAGUAUGUCUCAGGCCAUGAGGCAAAAGGAAAUGAGUAGUUCUUUUUGGUUGGAGAAUUAAAAAGAAAUCUCCACCCAAGUAACAGGUACAUAGUGGGAAAAAAUAACAUCUGCCUGAAAGCUUCAUCUUCAGGCAAAGAGAGGGUCAGGGGGCGGGAGCUUAGUAAUGGGGAAACCUCAGAAGAUUUAAAGAGAAUUACAGACAGACAAGGCUGAACAUUGGCUGUCAUCCAACAAAGCUCUUAUAAGAUGGGAAUCACUGCCCGGUUCUUGAGCUCCGACCUGGAGGGAAGAGGAGUCUGGAAGACUUGGCACAGGCCUGAGUGCUUCAUUGUCUUUCUGGUUCCAAGUCCUCCUCAGCUCACUAGGAAGGAGGUGGGGUGGGGGCAGGUAGGCCACUCUGCAUAAGUGCACACAUCUACACUGGCUAGUCUACUUCACAAUUCCCCCACAGGUUAUCCUUAUCUCUACCUGGUUCCAGUUCCAGAUUGGAGGGAUAUAGAAUACCAUCCCCACCCCUCACCUUGCUUGCUCUGGCCUGGAAAACUGUCAUUCCUUUACCACCAGCUGGCAUCUGCCAUAUGCUUCAAGGAACUGAAUAAAGAGGAAGGGGAAAGAAGAAACUAGAGAAACUGGAAUGCUUCCUAUCUGACCCCCAAGUACAGGGACUGCCUCUUUCCGUAACGGCACAGAACGUCUCCAUCCCUUUGACCUCCACCUCCCCAGAGAUGCCCGAGGAGGACAGCCUUGUUUCUGUGAUCUGUUGUUGAGAACUGCUGCUGAGAAUUCUUCCUUCAGCACCGCCUUAGGCACCAUUGGUUUUUCACUAGGUCCGCUGUAGAAAACAGCCAGGAAUUACUUAGUUGACUACCACCUGAGGUGCUGUUUGGUGUUGGUAAUAAAGAAUAAAGGUGGAAAUGAA